AGAGCUCGCCACUCCUUAGUCGAGGCAAGACGUGCGCCCGAGCCCCGCCGAACCGAGGCCACCCGGAGCCGUGCCCAGUCCACGCCGGCCGUGCCCGGCGGCCUUAAGAACCCGGCAACCUCUGCCUUCUUCCCUCUUCCACUCGGAGUCGCGCUCCGCGCGCCCUCACUGCAGCCCCUGCGUCGCCGGGACCCUCGCGCGCGACCGCCGAAUCGCUCCUGCAGCAGAGCCAACAUGCCCAUCACUCGGAUGCGCAUGAGACCCUGGCUAGAGAUGCAGAUUAAUUCCAACCAAAUCCCGGGGCUCAUCUGGAUUAAUAAAGAGGAGAUGAUCUUCCAGAUCCCAUGGAAGCAUGCUGCCAAGCAUGGCUGGGACAUCAACAAGGAUGCCUGUUUGUUCCGGAGCUGGGCCAUUCACACAGGCCGAUACAAAGCAGGGGAAAAGGAGCCAGAUCCCAAGACGUGGAAGGCCAACUUUCGCUGUGCCAUGAACUCCCUGCCAGAUAUCGAGGAGGUGAAAGACCAGAGCAGGAACAAGGGCAGCUCAGCUGUGCGAGUGUACCGGAUGCUUCCACCUCUCACCAAGAACCAGAGAAAAGAAAGAAAGUCGAAGUCCAGCCGAGAUGCUAAGAGCAAGGCCAAGAGGAAGUCAUGUGGGGAUUCCAGCCCUGAUACCUUCUCUGAUGGACUCAGCAGCUCCACUCUGCCUGAUGACCACAGCAGCUACACAGUUCCAGGCUACAUGCAGGACUUGGAGGUGGAGCAGGCCCUGACUCCAGCACUGUCGCCAUGUGCUGUCAGCAGCACUCUCCCCGACUGGCACAUCCCAGUGGAAGUUGUGCCGGACAGCACCAGUGAUCUGUACAACUUCCAGGUGUCACCCAUGCCCUCCACCUCUGAAGCUACAACAGAUGAGGAUGAGGAAGGGAAAUUACCUGAGGACAUCAUGAAGCUCUUGGAGCAGUCGGAGUGGCAGCCAACAAACGUGGAUGGGAAGGGGUACCUACUCAAUGAACCUGGAGUCCAGCCCACCUCUGUCUAUGGAGACUUUAGCUGUAAGGAGGAGCCAGAAAUUGACAGCCCAGGGGGGGAUAUUGGGCUGAGUCUACAGCGUGUCUUCACAGAUCUGAAGAACAUGGAUGCCACCUGGCUGGACAGCCUGCUGACCCCAGUCCGGUUGCCCUCCAUCCAGGCCAUUCCCUGUGCACCGUAGCAGGGCCCCUGGGCCCCUCUUAUUCCUCUAGGCAAGCAGGACCUGGCAUCAUGGUGGAUAUGGUGCAGAGAAGCUGGACUUCUGUGGGCCCCUCAACAGCCAAGUGUGACCCCACUGCCAAGUGGGGAUGGGGCCUCCCUCCUUGGGUCAUUGACCUCUCAGGGCCUGGCAGGCCAGUGUCUGGGUUUUUCUUGUGGUGUAAAGCUGGCCCUGCCUCCUGGGAAGAUGAGGUUCUGAGACCAGUGUAUCAGGUCAGGGACUUGGACAGGAGUCAGUGUCUGGCUUUUUCCUCUGAGCCCAGCUGCCUGGAGAGGGUCUCGCUGUCACUGGCUGGCUCCUAGGGGAACAGACCAGUGACCCCAGAAAAGCAUAACACCAAUCCCAGGGCUGGCUCUGCACUAAGAGAAAAUUGCACUAAAUGAAUCUCGUUCCCAAAGAACUACCCCCUUUUCAGCUGAGCCCUGGGGACUGUUCCAAAGCCAGUGAAAUGUGAAGGAAAGUGGGGUCCUUCGGGGCGAUGCUCCCUCAGCCUCAGAGGAGCUCUACCCUGCUCCCUGCUUUGGCUGAGGGGCUUGGGAAAAAAACUUGGCACUUUUUCGUGUGGAUCUUGCCACAUUUCUGAUCAGAGGUGUACACUAACAUUUCCCCCGAGCUCUUGGCCUUUGCAUUUAUUUAUACAGUGCCUUGCUCGGCGCCCACCACCCCCUCAAGCCCCAGCAGCCCUCAACAGGCCCAGGGAGGGAAGUGUGAGCGCCUUGGUAUGACUUAAAAUUGGAAAUGUCAUCUAACCAUUAAGUCAUGUGUGAACACAUAAGGACGUGUGUAAAUAUGUACAUUUGUCUUUUUAUAAAAAGUAAAUUGUUUAUAAGGGGUGUGGCCUUUUUAGAGAGAAAUUUAACUUGUAGAUGAUUUUACUUUUUAUGGAAACACUGAUGGACUUAUUAUUGGCAUCCCGCCUGAACUUGACUUUGGGGUGAACAGGGACAUGCAUCUAUUAUAAAAUCCUUUCGGCCAGGCGCGGUGGCUCACACCUGUAAUCCCAGCACUUUGGGAGGCCGAGAUGGGUGGAUCACCUGAGGUCAGGAGUUCGAGACCAGCCUGGUGAAACUCCAUUUCUACUAAAAAUGCAAAAAUUAGCUGGGCGUGGUUGCGGGUGCUUGUAAUCCCAGCUACUCAGGAGGCUGAGGCAAGAGAAUCGCUUGAACCUGGGAGGUGGAGGUUGCAGUGAGCCGAGAACAUGCCAUUGCACUCCAGCCCGGGCACCAAAAAAAAAAAAAAAAAAAAAAACCUUUCAUUUGGCCGGGCAUGGUGGCUUAUGCCUGUAAUCCUGGCACUUUGGGAGGCCAAGGUGGGCAGAUCACCUGAGGUCAGGAGUUUGAGACCAGCCUGGCCAACAUGGUGAAACCUCAUCUCUACUAAAAAUACAAAAAUUAGGCCGGGCACGGUGGCUCACGCCUGUAAUCCCAGCACUUUGGGAGGCAGAGGCGGGCGGAUCACGAGGUCAGGAGAUCAAGACCAUCCUGGCUAACACGGUGAAACCCCGUCUCUACUAAAAAUAUAAAAAAUUAGCCGGGCCUAGUGGCGGGUGCCUGUAGUCCCAGCUACUCGGGAGGCUGAGGCAGGAGAAUGGCAUGAACCCCGGAGGCAGAGCUUGCAGUGAGCCGAGAUUGCACCACUGCACUACAGCCUGGGCGACAGAGCGAGACUCCGUCUCAAAAAAAAAAAAAAAAAUUAGCCGGGCCUGGUGGCGGGCGCCUGUAAUCCCAGCUACUGUGGAGGCUGAAGCACAAGAAUCACUUGAACCCGGGAGAUGGAGGUUGCAGUGAGCUGAGACUGUGCCACUGCACUCCAGCCUGGGUGACAAGAGUGAGACUUUGUCUCAAAAAAAAAAAAAUCCUUUUGUUUAUGUUCACAUAGACAAUGGCAGAAGGAGGGGACAUUCCUGUCAUAGGAACAUGCUUAUAUAAACAUAGUCACCUGUCCUUGACUAUCACCAGGGCUGUCAGUUGAUUCUGGGCUCCUGGGGCCCAAGGAGUGUUAAGUUUUGAGGCAUGUGCCAUAGGUGAUGUGUCCUGCUAACACACAGAUGCUGCUCCAAAAAGUCAGUUGAUAUGACACAGUCACAGACAGAACAGUCAGCAGCCCAAGAAAGGUCCUCACGGCUGCUGUGCUGGGUAGCACUUGCCAUCCAGUUUCUAGAGUGAUGAAAUGCUCUGUCUGUACCGUUCAAUACAGUAGGCACUGGCACUAGCCACAUGUGCCAGCUAAGCACUUGAAAUGUGGCCAGUGCAAUAAGGAAUUGAACUUUUAAUUGCAUUUAAUAAACUGUAUGUAAAUAGUCA